GGCUGGCCUGUAACGGCUUGCACGCGCAUGCUGCACGCGGAUUGGAAACCCGGAGUUACCUGCUAGUUGGUGAAACUGGUUGGUAGACGUGAUCUGCUCGCUACUACCGGCCUCCCCAGGCUGUUAAAAGCAGAUGGUAGCUGAGGUUGAUUCAAUGCCGGCUGCCUCUUCUGUGAAGAAGCCAUUUGUUCUCAGGAGCAAGAUGGGCAAGUGGUGCCGCCACUGCUUCCCCUGCUGCAGGGGGAGCGGCAAGAGCAACGUGGGCACUUCUGGAGACCAGGACGACUCCACUAUGAAGACACUCAGGAGCAAGAUGGGCAAGUGGUGCUGCCACUGCUUCCCCUGCUGCAGGGGGAGUGGCAAGAGCAACGUGGGCACUUCUGGAGACCACGACGACUCCGCUAUGAAGACGCUCAGGAGCAAGAUGGGCAAGUGGUGCUGCCACUGCUUCCCCUGCUGCAGGGGGAGCGGCAAGAGCAACGUGGGUGCUUGGGGAGACUACGACGACAGCGCCUUCGUGGAGCCGAGAUACCACGUCCGUCGAGAAGAUCUGGACAAGCUCCACAGAGCUGCCUGGUGGGGUAAAGUCGCCAGAAAGGAUCUGAUCGUCAUGCUCAGGGACACUGACGUGAACAAGCAGGACAAGCAAAAGAGGACUGCUCUACAUCUGGCCUCUGCCAAUGGGAAUUCAGGAGUAGUAAAACUCCUGCUGGACAGACGAUGUCAACUUAAUGUCCUUGACAACAAAAAGAGGACAGCUCUGACAAAGGCCGUACAAUGCCAGGAAGAUGAAUGUGCGUUAAUGUUGCUGGAACAUGGCACUGAUCCAAACAUUCCAGAUGAGUAUGGAAAUACCACUCUACACUACGCUAUCUACAAUGAAGAUAAAUUAAUGGCCAAAGCACUGCUCUUAUACGGUGCUGAUAUCGAAUCAAAAAACAAGCAUGGCCUCACACCACUGCUACUUGGUGUACAUGAGCAAAAACAGCAAGUGGUGAAAUUUUUAAUCAAGAAAAAAGCGAAUUUAAAUGCGCUGGAUAGAUAUGGAAGAACUGCUCUCAUACUUGCUGUAUGUUGUGGAUCAGCAAGUAUAGUCAGCCUUCUACUUGAGCAAAAUAUUGAUGUAUCUUCUCAAGAUCUAUCUGGACAGACGGCCAGAGAGUAUGCUGUUUCUAGUCAUCAUCAUGUAAUUUGCCAGUUACUUUCUGACUACAAAGAAAAACAGAUGCUAAAAAUCUCUUCUGAAAACAGCAAUCCAGAACAAGACUUAAAGCUGACAUCAGAGGAAGAGUCACAAAGGUUCAAAGGCAGUGAAAAUAGCCAGCCAGAGAAAAUGUCUCAAGAACCAGAAAUAAAUAAGGAUGGUGAUAGAGAGGUUGAAGAAGAAAUGAAGAAGCAUGAAAGUAAUAAUGUGGGAUUACUAGAAAACCUGAGUAAUGGUGUCACUGCUGGCAAUGGUGAUGAUGGAUUAAUUCCUCAAAGGAAGAGCAGAACACCUGAAAAUCAGCAAUUUCCUGACAACGAAAGUGAAGAGUAUCACAGGUCGGGCAUGGUGGCUCACACCUGUAAUCACAGCACUUUGGGAGGCCGAGGCAGGCGGAUCACGAGAAUUUGCGAAUUAGUUUCUGACUACAAAGAAAAACAGAUGCCAAAAUACUCUUCUGAAAACAGCAACCCAGAACAAGACUUAAAGCUGACAUCAGAGGAAGAGUCACAAAGGCUUAAAGGCAGUGAAAAUGGCCAGCCAGAGAAAAGAUCUCAAGAACCAGAAAUAAAUAAGGAUGGUGAUAGAGAGCUAGAAAAUUUUAUGGCUAUCGAAGAAAUGAAGAAGCACGGAAGUACUCACGUCGGAUUCCCAGAAAACCUGACUAAUGGUGCCACUGCUGGCAAUGGUGAUGAUGGAUUAAUUCCUCCAAGGAAGAGCAGAACACCUGAAAGCCAGCAAUUUCCUGACACUGAGAAUGAAGAGUAUCACAGUGACGAACAAAAUGAUACUCAGAAGCAAUUUUGUGAAGAACAGAACACUGGAAUAUUACACGAUGAGAUUCUGAUUCAUGAAGAAAAGCAGAUAGAAGUGGUUGAAAAAAUGAAUUCUGAGCUUUCUCUUAGUUGUAAGAAAGAAAAAGACUUCUUGCAUGAAAAUAGUACGUUGCGGGAAGAAAUUGCCAUGCUAAGACUGGAGCUAGACACAAUGAAACAUCAGAGCCAGCUAAGAAAAAAGAAAUAUUUGGAGGAUAUUGAAAGUGUGAAAAAAAAGAAUGAUAAUCUUUUAAAGGCUCUACAAUUGAAUGAGCUCACCAUGGAUGAUGAUACCGCCGUGCUCGUCAUUGACAACGGCUCUGGCAUGUGCAAGGCCGGCUUUGCGGGCGACGAUGCCCCCCGGGCUGUCUUCCCUUCCAUCGUGGGGCGCCCCAGGCAGCAGGGCAUGAUGGGGGGCAUGCAUCAGAAAGAGUCCUAUGUGGGCAAGGAGGCCCAGAGCAAGAGAGGCAUCCUGACCCUGAAGUACCCCAUGGAACACGGCAUCAUCACCAACUGGGAUGACAUGGAGAAGAUCUGGCACCACACCUUCUACAACGAGCUGCGUGUGGCCCCUGAGGAGCACCCCAUCCUGCUGACCGAGGCCCCCCUGAACCCCAAGGCCAACCGCGAGAAGAUGACCCAGAUCAUGUUUGAGACCUUCAACACCCCAGCCAUGUACGUGGCCAUCCAGGCCAUGCUGUCCCUGUACACCUCUGGCCGUACUACUGGCAUCGUGAUGGACUCUGGUGACGGGGUCACCCACACUGUGCCCAUCUAUGAUGGGAAUGCCCUCCCCCAUGCCACCCUGCGCCUAGACCUGGCUGGGCGGGAACUGACUGACUACCUCAUGAAGAUCCUCACCGAGCGUGGCUAUAGGUUCACCACCAUGGCCGAGCGGGAAAUCGUGCGUGACAUCAAAGAGAAGCUGUGCUAUGUUGCCCUGGACUUCGAGCAGGAGAUGGCCAUGGCGGCCUCCAGCUCCUCCCUAGAGAAGAGCUACGAGCUGCCCGAUGGCCAGGUCAUCACCAUCGGCAACGAGUGGUUCCGCUGCCCCGAGGCGCUCUUCCAGCCUUGCUUCCUGGGCAUGGAAUCCUGUGGCAUCCAUGAAACUACCUUCAACUCCAUCAUGAAGUCUGAUGUGGACAUCCGCAAAGACCUGUACACCAACACAGUGCUGUCUGGCGGCACCACCAUGUACCCUGGCAUGGCCCACAGAAUGCAGAAGGAGAUCGCUGCCCUGGCGCCUAGCAUGUUGAAGAUCAGGAUCAUUGCUCCUCCCAAGCGCAAGUACUCCGUGUGGGUCGGUGGCUCCAUCCUGGCCUCGCUGUCCACCUUCCAGCAGAUGUGGAUCAGCAAGCAGGAGUAUGAUGAGUCAGGCCCCUCCAUUGUCCACCGCAAAUGCUUCUAGGUGGACUCUGACUUAGUUGCGUUACACCCUUUCUUGACAAAACCAAACUUCUCAGAAAACAACAUGAGAUUGGCAUGGCUUUAUUUGUUUUCUUGUUUCAUUUUUUGUUUUGUUUUUUAUUGGCUUGACUCAGGAUUUAAAAACCGGAAUGGUGAAGGUGACAGCAGUCGGUUGGAGGAAGCUUCCUCCAAAGUUCUACAAUGUGGCCAAGGACUUUGAUUGUACAUUGUUCUUCUUUUCAAUAGUCAUUCCAAAUAUUGUGAGACGCAUUGUUUCAGGAAGCCCCUUGCCCUGCUAAAAGCCACCCCACUUCUCUCUAAGGAGAAUGGCCCAGUCCUCUCCCUAGUUCACACAGGGGAGGUGAUAGCAUUGCUUUUGUGCAGAUUACAUAAUGCAAAAUUUUUUGAAUCUUCGCCUUAAUACUUUUUAAUUUUGUUUUAUUUUGAAUGAUCAGCCUUCGUGGCCCCCCUCUUUUGUACCCCAACUUGGGGUGUAUGAAGGCUUUUGGUCUCCCUGAGAGUGGCUGGAGGCAGCCAGGGCUUACCUGUACUCUGACUUGAGGAGAGUUGGAUAAAAGUGCACACCUUAAAAAAAAUUGAGGAAGCACAGUAUUUCAGUACAGUGGACAGCUUAGCAUGUUGACAACUGAGAAUAAAAUGCUCAGUUCUGAACUGGACAAUGUAAGACACAACGAGGAAACACCGGAAAUGGAAAUUCAAUUACGUCAUUGUAGACUGGCUGCUGCUCUACAUGAUUGUGACCAAAGUCAGAUAGCUGAAAGAGACUUCUUUCCAGAGAACAAGACAUGAACAGGUUUAUUUACAGAAGACAAUGAAUUCUCAUUUAUCUCACCUAAAAGAGAACAGAUUCUUUCUCAACAAGUCUAACGUAGACAGUAAAAUCAACAGGCUAAAAAUUAAGCUCCAUGAAACAAGAUAAAACUCUGAGAGAAAAGACGGGGCAGGCCGCCAUCUUUCCCGUUCAGGCAACUUAGUCAUUCCAGCCUGCGGGCUUUGGAGAGUACAAACCGACGAGGGACAGAAGAGAUCCCACAGCACAGCAUAGCUGCUUUACCAAAUCAUGGCCAGACUGCUUCUGUAAGCAGGCCCCUGAUCCUGUUCCAUCUCACUGGACAGGACCUCCCAACUGGGGCCUCCAGCUACCCCCACCAGCAUUCCUUGGCCAAUGGAAAUGUGAAAUGUUCCUGGGACAGAGCUCCCGGAGAGGGGCAGGCCCCCACCUUUGCUCUUUCGGUGACUAGCCAUUCUGGCCUGCGGGCUUUGGAGAGCCCAAGCUGACAAGGGGUGGAAGAGGUACCUCAGCACAGCACAGCCACGCUACCAAAACGUGGCCAGACUCUUGUUUACGUCAGUCCCUGACCACAUUUCUAGUCAGUGGGUGAAGUCUUUCAACCAGGGUCUCUGGCUACCUUGACUGCUGUUCUCUGGCCGACAGAGGUCUCAGGCCUCCCUGAGUCAGAGCUCCCAGGGGGAGGACCAGAUUGUCAUCUUUGCUGUUGGGGCGACCCAGGCAUUUCAGCCUUAGGGCUUCAGAGUGUCUGAGGCGGACCAGGGGCUGAAGUGAACCCCCAGCACAGCACAGCUGCUCUAUAAAAACGUGGCCAGACUUUUCUUUUUGAAGCAAGUCCCUGUUCUUGUUCGUCCUGACUAGGUAAGACUUCUCAACUUGCCUCCAGCCACAUCUUAUAGGUGUGUUCAGAUUGGCAACAGGUUCGUACCUCAGUGGUACAGAGCUUCCAGAGGAAGGGGCAGACUAUCAUCUUCCCUGGAAAAUACAAGGCAAUUAGGGACUGGAGGGGACCCCCAGCAUACCACAGCAGCCCUACAGAAAAGUGGCCAGGCUCUCUACUUGAUGGGCAGAUCCUCCUGGCCUGGGUCUCUAGCCAGCCCACCACUGGAGCUAUCAAGCCAGUAGCAACUCUGCAGUUCCUGGGACAGAGCUUCCAGGAGCAAAUGAAAUCCUUUCUGCCACUGCCUCUGCAGUGGAACUGCCCUUGCUGCCCUCAGAAGAUGCAAGGGAGCAAAGACCCUAAGUGCCCUAUCAACACCUCCAAUAAGCUGCAGUUGACCCAAAGAACAAGCCAGUCCAUCUCCCACGGGUACCACACACCCUCCACUACUCAUCACCAGACAGGGAACCCUGGCUUGGGCCCACAGCACAGACCCUCCAUCCUGGGCUGAUUACACUAAGUGAUUGCUAACUCACAUGUCUCUGGGAUGGAGCACCCAGGAAACAAGCAAAGUGGUGGAGCAGCAAGUCAGGUGAUGUGGAGCCCAGAGGUCAGGGAUGGCUGUCUCUCUAGGGUCCACUUGCCCUUGUGAGACACUUUAUCCCAGCACUUUAGGAAUACUGAGGUCAUACCAGCCACAUCUUAUAUGCAAGAUUGCCCAGCAGAGAUCAGGUCCGAGAGUUCCCUUUUUAAAAAAAGGAGACUUGCUUAAUAAAAGAAGUCUAGCCACGUUUGUGUAGAGCGGCUGUGCUGUGCUGGGGGUUCACUUUUGAGAGAGUUCUCCUCUGAGACCUGAUCUCUGGAGGCUGGGCAAUCUUGCACUUGAGAUGGGGCUGGUCUGAUCUCAGCACUCCUUAGUCUGCUCGCCUCUCCCAUGGCCCCAGCCUGGCCACACCUGCUUACGGGGCACUCUUAGAUGCCCACACCAUAGCUUCCGUGCUAGUGGACUGUACCAUAUCAGUGGAGAGCUGCAGCAAGGUGGCCCCUAGAGCCACGCACCAGCCUGCACAUUGCCUCUCCAUACGGCAGCCCUUUAUUUGGAAACUUCCUAAAUCACUUUGCUGUGUGUGUUUACACGGGUGGGUUUUGCUUUACUUGCCCUGAGAGCACACAGGAGUGCAGCACACACCCCAACCCACAUCAACUGCCAUUAAAGAAAAGAAAUUUCAGCCCAGAAUUUCAUGUCCAGCAAAAUUAAGCAUCAUAAGUGAAGGAGAAAUAAGAUCCUUUUCAGACAAGCAAGUGCUGAGGGAAUUUGGUAUCACCAGAUCUACCUUACGAGAGCUCCUGAAGGAAGCACUAAAUAUGGAAAGAAAAGAUCAUCACCUGCUACUACAAAAACACACUGAAGUACACAGUCCAAUGAUGCUAAAAAGCAAGCACAUAUGUAAGUCUGCAAAAUAACCAGCUGACAGCAUGACGACAGGAUAAAAUCCACACAUACCAUUACUAACCUUAAAUGUAAAUGGGCUAAAUGCUCCCAUUGAAAGACACGGGGCAAGCUGGGUAAAGAACCAAGACCCACUGGAGUAUGCCGUCUUCAAGCAACCCAUCUCACGUGCAGUGCCAUACAUAGGCUCAAAAUAAAGGAAUGGAGAAAAAUAUUUCAAG